CGCCUGUAGUAUACCUCUAAGUAUACUAGAACUAUGUUGAUGUUUUCCUCUCUCUGCCUUGGCCACUAGGAAGCUCAGAGUCAAGUUUGUAUCCAGGGUCUUCCAGCUUGUGCUUAAGUGUUUUAAUCGUCUAGAUUGUUUUUAAUGGUUUCUGCUCUUUGUCUCAGGUUUUACUAUAAAAUACAUAACACAUUUCCUUCCCGUUCUAAAUAUUACUGUGAUUGUAUUCUUAUAGCCAAAUCUUUGUUCUUAUUCUUAUUUUAUUUUAUUUUUUAUACUGUUGAAUCCCUCUGAGCCUUGCCUUUCCCUGCCUCCUCUUCUGUACUCAUUUUUGCUAAAAUUUGUAAGGGGAUAAAUUCUUGAAAAGCUUUGCACAUUUUGAAGACUUGUUUGUUUUUUAAUAUUUAUUAUAGUAAAACUCAAAUAUACAUCCAAAUAGAGAGCAAUAAGCCCUUGUGUACCUAUCACUCAGUUAUGUCUGUCACUUAGUCAUUAACUUGGGGACACUCUUGUUUCAUCUAUAUCCUUUAAUCCUCAUUAUACUUUUUUUUGGGGGGAGAAGUUUAUUAAUUGAUAGGUGUUACUUUGGGGUAAAUGAGGAGGGAGCCCACUAGUAUGCUGGGGAACUGGUAAGGUUUUUUUGUUUUUUUCUUGAAACAGAGUCUUGCUCUUGUCGCCCAGGCUGGAGUGCAGUGGUGCGAUCUCGGCUCACUGCAACCUUCGCCCCCCUGGGUUCAAGCGACUCUCCUGCCUCAGCCUCCCAAGUAGCUGGGAUUACAGGCACCUGCCACCACACCUGGCUAGUUUUUGUACUUUUAGUAGAUGGGAUUUCACCAUGUUGGCCAGGCUAGUCUUGAACUCCUGACCUCCGGUGAUCUGCCUGCCUCGGCCUCCCAAAGUGUUGGGAUUAUAGGCGUGAGCCACUGCGCCCCGCAAAGGUUCUUUUCUUUGGGAUCCUUUCCUGUCCUUAGAGAAGACCCUUUAGCUUUCUGCCUGAGGAGCUGAUGCCUAGUUGUCAGGCUUUCUUCUUGCCCAGAUAAGGGUGUUAACUCCUGUGUACAGAUGUUCACUUAAUCCUUUUUACCAGUCCCACAUCUCACUAUAGCCCUAUGCUACACCUGGGUUUCUCCAUCCCAAGCCCCUUUAGGGUCUCUAGUGCCAGUCUUCUUCCUCAUUGGCUAUGUCCCCUAGGUUCUUUUUUAUUUUUCCCAACGGUGAUGCACUUACUGAGCAGAUGCAGUAAUCUUCUUACCUGAGCCUACAUAUAACCAUUGGCCUAAAUGUAUGAUGGUUUGCCAGCAUCAGCAAUAAGACUGGUAAUGGGGUAAAAAACAAGUUCUCUUAAGGCUAGCUCUUGAUCCCCUGUUGUAAGCUGACCAACUUAAUCUGAAAAUAAUUUGCAGCAUGUAAAUAUUUUAGGAUUAGAGCCAUCUGUAUACACACUUAAAAGUAGUUUUGCUACCAUUACAUUAGUCUAAAAGAGUUACCUAAGAAUGCCAAACGAUAUUUUGUUCGAAUGCCUUGGUUAUUUUAAUUUAAAAGCAUUUCUUUCAAAACCGCUUCUCUCUUCACAAUAGUAGAGCUGUGGCAGUGAACUAAGAGGUCAAGGAUUCAGUGAAUCUGUGGCUAAUUUCUUGUUCCAAUCUGAGAGCUCUCUUUGCACUAUGAUCAAAAUGGAGUCUUGCCAACUGCCCAGGGUAAUAGCCUUGCAAGUCUCUUCCUUGUUGAGCAAUGAAUAUAAGUUCCACAUGGCUGGGGAGGCCUCACAAUCAUGGCAGAAGGUGAAAGAGGAGCAAAGGCAUGUCUUACAUGGUGGCAGGCAAGCCUCUUCUCAUUAUACUUUUAAAAUUAUUUGGUGGCUGGGUGCAGUGGCUCAUGCCUGUAAUCCCAGCACUUUGGGAGGCCAAGGUGGGUGGAUCACUUGAGGUCAGAAGUUCAAGACCAGCUUGGCCAACAUGGUGAAACCUUGCCUGUACUAAAAAUACAAAAAUUAGCAGGGUCAUGGUGGCACGCACCUGUAAUUCUAGCUACUUGGGAAGCUGAGGAAGAAUUGUUUGGACCCAGAGGUAAAGGUUGCAGUGAGCCAGGAUCGUGUCACAGCACUCCAGCCUGGGUGACCGAACAAGACUCUCAAAACAAACAAACAAAAAUUAUUUGGUGAUUUUUUUUUUGAGACGGAGUCUCCUUGUCACUCAAGCUGGAAUGCAACGGCGUGGUCUCUGCUCACCGCAACCUUUGCCUCCCGGUUCAAGCGAUUCUUCUGUCUCAGCUUACCAAGUAGCUGGGACUACAGGCAUGUGCCACCACACCCGGCUAAUUUUUGUAUUUUUUGUAGAGAUAGGGUUUCACCAUGUUGGCCAGGCUGGUCUUGAACUCCUGACCUCAAGUGAUCUGCCCACCUUGGCAUCCCCAAGUGCUGGGAUUGCAGGUGUGAGCCAACGUGCCUGGCCCAUUUUAACCAUUUUUAAGUGUACUAUUUAGUGACAUUAAAUGUAUUCACAUUGUUAUGCAACCAUCAUCACUAUCCAUUUCCAGAAUGUUUUCAUUAUUCUACAUAGAAACUAUCGAUCCAGGAGCCAUAUGUAGAAAGCUGAAACUGGAUCCCUUCCUUACACCUUAUACAAAAAUCAAUUCAAGAUGGAUUAAAGACUUAAAUGUUAGACCUAAAACCAUAAAAACCCUAGAAGAAAACCUAGGCAAUACCAUUCAGGCCAUAGGCAUGGGCAAGGACUUCAUGACUAAAACACCAAAAGCAAUGGCAACAAAAGCCAAAAUUGACAAAUGGGAUCUAAUUAAACUAAAGAGCUUCUACACAGCAAAAGAAACUACCAUCAGACUGAACAGGCAACCUACAGAGUGGGAGAAAAUUUUUACAAUCUACCCAUCUGACAAAGGGCUAAUAUCCAGAAUCUACAAAGAACUUAAACAGAUUUACAAGAAAAAAAUCAAACAACCCUAUCAAAAAGUGGGUGAAGCAUAUGAACAGACACUUCUCAAAAGAAGACAUUUAUGCAGCCAACAGACACAUGAAAAAAUGCUUGUCGUCACUGGCCAUCAGAGAAAUGCAAAUCAAAACCACAAUGAGAUACCCUCACACCAGUUAGAAUGGGGAUCAUUAAAAAGUCAGGAAACAACAGGUGCUGGAGAGGAUGUGGAGAAAUAGGAACCCUUUUACACUGUUGGUGGGACUGUAAACUAGUUCAACCAUUGUGGAAGACAGUGUGGCGAUUCCUCAAGGAUCUAGAACUAGAAAUACCAUUUGACCCAGCCAUCCCAUUACUGGGCAUAUACCCAAAGGAUUAUAAAUCAUGCUGCUAUAAAGGCACAUGCACACGUAUGUUUAUUACGGCACUAUUCACAAUAGCAAAGACUUGGAACCAACCCAAAUGUCCAUCAAUGAUAGACUGGAUUAAGAAAAUGUGGCACAUAUACACCAUGGAAUACUAUGCAGCCAUAAAAAAAGGUUAGAUGGGUAGUGCUGACAUCAUAACAAGGUUCAAGAAUGACUCAUCUCACAUGUGUGUGAAACACCCAGGAGUCAUCUUUGAGUCUGGGUUUUCAUCAGUGAGUACAGUCAAGCCAAGAAAUGUGUCUGGGCAGGUUCCCUCUAGCACAGACCGAAGAAAACAGCAACAUGGAACAAGAGAAGUACCUGCACAUGUUGUUCUUUGUCAGUGCUGUCAAGUGUGUGCCAGGGUGAUCCAUGGUCACUUUCCGGGAUGGCAGCAAGGUGACUUCGGCUGAGGAUGACCCUGACUGAAAGGCUGCGUGAGAAGAUAUCUCGGGCCUUCUACAACCAUGGGCUCCUCUGUGCAUCCUAUCCCAUCCCCAUCAUCCUCUUCACAGGGUUCUGCAUCUUAGCCUGCUGCUACCCACUGCUGAAACUCCCCUUGCCAGGAACAGGACCUGUGGAAUUCACCACCCCUGUGAAGGAUUACUCGCCCCCACCUGUGGACUCUGACCGCAAACAAGGAGAGCCUACUGAGCAGCCUGAGUGGUAUGUGGGUGCCCCGGUGGCUUAUGUCCAGCAGAUAUUUGUGAAGUCCUCAGUGUUUCCCUGGCACAAGAACCUCCUGGCAGUAGAUGUAUUUCGUUCACCUUUGUCCCGGGCAUUCCAACUGGUGGAGGAGAUCCGGAACCACGUGCUGAGAGACAGCUCUGGGAUCAGGAGCUUGGAGGAGUUGUGUCUGCAAGUGACCGACCUGCUGCCAGGCCUUAGGAAGCUCAGGAACCUACUCCCUGAGCAUGGAUGCCUGCUGCUGUCCCCUGGGAACUUCUGGCAGAAUGACUGGGAACGCUUCCAUGCUGAUCCUGACAUCAUUGGGACCAUCCACCAGCACGAGCCUAAAACCCUGCAGACUUCAGCCACACUCAAAGACUUGUUAUUUGGUGUUCCUGGGAAGUACAGCGGGGUGAGCCUCUACACCAGGAAGAGGAUGGUCUCCUACACCAUCACCCUGGUCUUCCAGCACUACCAUGCCAAGUUCCUGGGCAGCCUGCGUGCCCGCCUGAUGCUUCUGCACCCCAGCCCCAACUGCAGCCUUCGGGCGGAGAGCCUGGUCCACGUGCACUUCAAGGAGGAGAUUGGUGUCGCUGAGCUCAUCCCCCUUGUGACCACCUACAUCAUCUUGUUUGCCUACAUCUACUUCUCCACGCGGAAGAUCGACAUGGUCAAGUCCAAGUGGGGGCUGGCCCUGGCUGCCGUGGUCACAGUGCUCAGCUCGCUGCUCAUGUCUGUGGGACUCUGCACACUCUUCGGCCUGACGCCCACCCUCAAUGGCGGCGAGAUUUUCCCCUACCUUGUGGUGGUUAUUGGGUUAGAGAAUGUGUUGGUGCUCACCAAGUCUGUGGUCUCAACCCCGGUAGACCUGGAGGUGAAGCUGCGGAUCGCCCAAGGCCUAAGCAGCGAGAGCUGGUCCAUCAUGAAGAACAUGGCCACGGAGCUGGGCAUCAUCCUCAUCGGCUACUUCACCCUAGUGCCCGCCAUCCAGGAGUUCUGUCUCUUUGCUGUCGUGGGGCUGGUGUCUGACUUCUUCCUUCAGAUGCUGUUUUUCACCACUGUCCUGUCCAUUGACAUUCGCCGGAUGGAGCUAGCAGACCUGAACAAGCGACUGCCCCCUGAGGCCUGCCUGCCCUCAGCCAAGCCAGUGGGACAGCCAACGCGCUACGAGCGGCAGCUGGCUGUGAGGCCGUCCACACCCCACACCAUCACGUUGCAGCCGUCUUCCUUCCGAAACCUGCGGCUCCCCAAGAGGCUGCGUGUUGUCUACUUCCUGGCCCGCACCCGCCUGGCACAGCGCCUCAUCAUGGCUGGCACCGUUGUCUGGAUUGGCAUCCUGGUAUACACAGACCCAGCAGGGCUGCGCAACUACCUCGCUGCCCAGGUGACGGAACAGAGCCCAUUGGGUGAGGGAGCCCUGGCUCCCAUGCCCGUGCCUAGUGGCAUGCUGCCCCCCAGCCACCCGGACCCUGCCUUCUCCAUCUUCCCACCUGAUGCCCCUAAGCUACCUGAGAACCAGACGUCGCCAGGCGAGUCACCUGAGCGUGGAGGUCCAGCAGAGGUUGUCCAUGACAGCCCAGUCCCAGAGGUAACCUGGGGGCCUGAGGAUGAGGAACUUUGGAGGAAAUUGUCCUUCCGCCACUGGCCGACGCUCUUCAGCUAUUACAACAUCACACUGGCCAAGAGGUACAUCAGCCUGCUGCCCGUCAUCCCAGUCACGCUCCGCCUGAACCCGAGGGAGGCUCUGGAGGGCCGGCACCCUCAGGACGGCCGCAGUGCCUGGCCCCCACCGGGGCCCAUACCUGCUGGGCACUGGGAAGCAGGACCCAAGGGCCCAGGUGGGGUGCAGGCCCAUGGAGACGUCACGCUGUACAAGGUGGCGGCGCUGGGCCUGGCCACCGGCAUCGUCUUGGUGCUGCUGCUGCUCUGCCUCUACCGCGUGCUAUGCCCGCGCAACUACGGGCAGCUGGGUGGUGGGCCCGGGCGGCGGAGGCGCGGGGAGCUGCCCUGCGACGACUACGGCUAUGCGCCACCCGAGACGGAGAUCGUGCCGCUUGUGCUGCGCGGCCACCUCAUGGACAUCGAGUGCCUGGCCAGCGACGGCAUGCUGCUGGUGAGCUGCUGCCUGGCAGGCCACGUCUGCGUGUGGGACGCGCAGACCGGGGAUUGCCUAACGCGCAUUCCGCGCCCAGGGCAGCGCCGGGACAGUGGCGUGGGCAGCGGGCUUGAGGCUCAGGAGAGCUGGGAACGACUUUCAGAUGGUGGGAAGGCUGGUCCAGAGGAGCCUGGGGACAGCCCUCCCCUGAGACACCGCCCCCGGGGCCCUCCGCCGCCUUCCCUCUUCGGGGACCAGCCUGACCUCACCUGCUUAAUUGACACCAACUUUUCAGCGCAGCCUCGGUCCUCACAGCCCACUCAGCCCGAGCCCCGGCACCGGGCGGUCUGUGGCCGCUCUCGGGACUCCCCAGGCUAUGACUUCAGCUGCCUGGUGCAGCGGGUGUACCAGGAGGAGGGGCUGGCGGCCGUCUGCACACCAGCCCUGCGCCCACCCUCGCCUGGGCCGGUGCUGUCCCAGGCCCCUGAGGACGAGGGUGGCUCCCCCGAGAAAGGCUCCCCUUCCCUCGCCUGGGCCCCCAGUGCCGAGGGUUCCAUCUGGAGCUUGGAGCUGCAGGGCAACCUCAUCGUGGUGGGGCGGAGCAGCGGCCGGCUGGAGGUGUGGGACGCCAUUGAAGGGGUGCUGUGCUGCAGCAGCGAGGAGGUCUCCUCAGGCAUUACCGCUCUGGUGUUCUUGGACAAAAGGAUUGUGGCUGCACGGCUCAACGGUUCCCUUGAUUUCUUCUCCUUGGAGACCCACACUGCCCUCAGCCCCCUGCAGUUUAGAGGGACCCCAGGGCGGGGCAGUUCCCCUGCCUCUCCAGUGUACAGCAGCAGCGACACAGUGGCCUGUCACCUGACCCACACAGUGCCCUGUGCACACCAAAAACCCAUCACAGCCCUGAAAGCCGCUGCUGGGCGCUUGGUGACUGGGAGCCAAGACCACACACUGAGAGUGUUCCGUCUGGAGGACUCGUGCUGCCUCUUCACCCUUCAGGGCCACUCAGGGGCCAUCACGACCGUGUACAUUGACCAGACCAUGGUGCUGGCCAGUGGAGGACAAGAUGGGGCCAUCUGCCUGUGGGAUGUACUGACUGGCAGCCGGGUCAGCCAUGUGUUUGCUCACCGUGGGGAUGUCACCUCCCUUACCUGUACCACCUCCUGUGUCAUCAGCAGUGGCCUGGAUGACCUCAUCAGCAUCUGGGACCGCAGCACAGGCAUCAAGUUCUACUCCAUUCAGCAGGACCUGGGCUGUGGUGCAAGCUUGGGUGUCAUCUCAGACAACCUGCUGGUGACUGGCGGCCAGGGCUGUGUCUCCUUUUGGGACCUAAACUACGGGGACCUGUUACAGACAGUCUACCUGGGGAAGAACAGUGAGGCCCAGCCUGCCCGCCAGAUCCUGGUGCUGGACAACGCUGCCAUUGUCUGCAACUUUGGCAGUGAGCUCAGCCUGGUGUAUGUGCCCUCUGUGCUGGAGAAGCUGGACUGAGCGCAGGGCCUCCUUGCCCAGGCAGGAGGCUGGGGUGCUGUGUGGGGGCCAAUGCACUGAACCUGGACUUGGGGGAAAGAGCCGAGUAUCUUCCAGCCGCUGCCUCCUGACUGUAAUAAUAUUAAACUUUUUUAAAAAACCAUAUCAUCAUCUGUCAGGCACUUUGGGAGCUA